UCUCAAAAACAAACAAAACAAAAGAAAAGCAAGAGGAGGCAAGGAGCGGGGUGGGUAGGGGAACCCCUUAGUUCCUGGUUUGCAAGAGCAGUGGGUGCAGGGAGUGGGGUCUGAGUAUGUAGUGGGGAAGAACCCGGUCUCCUGUGGGGGAUGCAGUCCCCCUGCACUUUCUGGCUUUGGCAUCUGCCAGGCCCUUUUGGCAUCUGCGAGUCCCAGGCCUGAGGUGUGGGGCAGGAGGAGGGAGGCUGAGAUGGAGGAGGGAGGGUCGCCCAGGGCUGGAUGAAAGCCGCAGGGAAAUGCACACCAGAUGAGGUGGGCUCCACAAGGAGGGGGGCAGUCCUCAGAGCAACUUGUCAGAUGUUUGUCACACGGGGGUCCAGUCCUGCUCCUCUCCCUCCUCCCCCGUCUCUCCCACCCUCAUCCACACCUGGGCUAGGAUAGGCUUCGGAUGCCUGGGGAGGGAAAGUAAUUGAUCCCAAAGAUCUCCGAUCUCUGAGCUGGUUUGUGCAAGAGGGGGCCUCGAAAGCCCUUGCCGCCUGUCUGUGUUCCCACUCCCCUUCCACGGCAGGGGGUCCGGGAACCCCAUCCCCCUACGGAGCUCCCUCUGACUCUUUGGAGAGAAGGCCUGGCAGGGUGAACUUUCCUGUUUUGGUGCUGGUCCCUCCAGCAGGCAGGAAGAGGAGGAUAUUCAGAGUCACUGGUGUGCCAUCUGGGAAAGGAAAGGGGUGGGCUCCUGGUCUCGCUUGGUGCCUGGGGUCAGUAUGCCCGAGACGGGAGGGAAGGGCCUGGGGCUUCCUUCCUGGCCGAGGGGAAAAGCAGGCAGUGACUUCUCAUGAGGCCUGGGGUCUUUCCCCUCCCAGCACUGGCCUGGUUUCUCUCUAUGGGCAUCGUCAGCGAGGUCCCGUGGUGGGGGGUGGUGCCUCCCCUUCUUGACCUCUCUCAGGGACGGGGGUGCCCCUGAGCUGCCAGGCCUCAGACCUUGGUACCGCCACCACCCAAGGCCUCUGUGUUUGUCCCUGGGACGCUGGGUGCGGCUCCCACGCGGGUUCCAGCUGCAGGAGGUGGGGCGGGGAGUGCAGGGGCUCUGGGACUGACACCACCCUUCCAGGUGGGCUGGAAGGAGGCAGCCCUCCAGGGUGGGAAGAGGGAGGGCUGAGCCCCACGCUCAUCCCCAGCACCCCUGCCCCUCCCAGUCUCCCUGUGGCUGCUUCUGAAGUGGCAGUGGGUGGGUGGAGGGAGUCCCAGCUCCCUCUGUCACCAAGACGGAGGAGGACUUGUCCGGUAUCGUCUGUAGGCCAGCUCUGCCCAGGGCCUGGUUCUGCGGGGUGGGAAGGCUCCCGUGCCGCCCACCCCUACUCUGCACCGCUCAUGGUGGGUGUUGUGGGGGAAGCCUGGAUUCUCUCCCGCUGCCUCACACAUCCUCCCUCCCACCUCCAGCGCUCUCCACCGAGCACCCCACUGCAGGGGUCUGUGCAGCUGCCUCUGGCCCAGCCUGCGUUUCCCUGGGGGUCUGAGCAGGAAAAGGGGACUCAGAACCUGCCUCCCAAGGGCUCAAGUCUGGGGCGGUCACUCCUGGCAGGUCAGCCUCCUGGCAGGGGCCGGUCCUGGGGCUGUCAGCAGGGGUGGGGGAAGCCCCCUCAGAGGGCAGGAGUCAGGGCUGGGCGUGACUGGCAAGGCAUCCCCUCCCUAACACAGUCCCUGUGUUUCUAUCGACCUAGUUCCCAGCCCUCCCCAGCUCUCCCUCCGAGCUGUUUGCUCAGCUGACCUACCACGCCCUGCCCUGCCCAACCUCACCCUGCACUACCUGGCUGGCAGGUGCUGCCCGGGGCACUGCUGGGGGUGCCUGGGCCUGCCCGGGCUGGGCACCCAGAAUGGGCUCUCUGCCCAGGUGGGACAGUCCUGGGCUGUGGUCGGCUGAUUCCCCCGGGACCUUGGGACUGGGUCAGUGCCCUCCUCUCCUGUGUCAGAAUGAGGAGAAUCUCAGAAAGGCCCCCUCCCUGGCCUGGCACCCUGGCAACCUGCAAGAUCUAGGGGGCCACAGCGGCCCAGGGUCUUGGGAAGGAUCCUCCGGCCGGCGCCGCCACGUCUCCGACUUUCCUCACAUGUGCUGGGCUCUGCUGGAGUCUGAUGCCCCGAACCCUGGAUGGGCAGAUCACCAUGGAGAAGACCCCCAGCUACUUCGUGACGCGAGAGGCCCCCCGCCGCAUCCACGCCAUGUCCCCGGACACGAAGCUGAUCGUGGUGGUGCGGAACCCCGUGACCCGGGCCAUCUCCGACUACGCCCAGACGCUCUCCAAGACCCCGGGCCUGCCCAGCUUCCGCGCCCUGGCCUUCCGCCACGGCCUGGGCCCCGUGGACACAGCCUGGAGCGCCGUCCGCAUCGGCCUGUACGCCCAGCACCUGGACCACUGGCUGCGCUACUUCCCCCUGUCCCACUUCCUGUUCGUCAGCGGGGAGCGUCUGGUCAGCGACCCGGCCGGAGAGGUCGGCCGCGUGCAGGACUUCCUGGGCCUGAAACGGGUCGUCACGGACAAGCACUUCUACUUCAACGCCACCAAGGGCUUCCCCUGCCUCAAGAAGGCCCAGGGCGGCAGCCGUCCCCGCUGCCUGGGCAAGUCCAAGGGCCGGCCACACCCACGCGUGCCCCAGGCCCUGGUCCGGCGCCUGCAGGAGUUCUACCGGCCCUUCAACCGCAGGUUCUACCAGAUGACGGGCCAGGACUUCGGCUGGGGCUGAGCGGCACCCUGGGGAUGCUCAGCACCUUGAUUGACACCCGCUCGCCUGGCCAGAGCGGGCUGCGUGCACAUGCUGGGCAGAGAGGAAUAUUUAAGAAAUAAAGCUUGGACCCAGA